AGAUUGAGCGCAGAACUAACCGCGCUCUGAAAGGUUCUAAAUGUCUGCGGGGCUCAGAGCCGGAUGUCACGUCGUCCUCCUCUGCCGGUUUUCUCUUGGGUCCUUUUCCGUGCCGUCCCGCGACUCCGCCUCUGGCCGCGCGUGUCUGGCUGCUAGGCCGACACCAAGGACUGGCCGGGUACCCGGGAAGAAAGCACGUGCUCCAGCAGUUGCCGCGCCCAGCCCCGAGAGAGGCCCUAGGGCGCUGCGGGCUUUCGGGGUCCGCAGUCCCCCCGCGACGCGAGCCAACGGGAGGCGUCAAAAGACCCGGGCCUUGUGUGGCAGGCUCGCCUGGCGCUGGCUGGCGUGGCCCUUGGCCGUCGUCACCUGUGGAGAGCACGUCUUCUCUGCCGCGCCCUCUGCGCAAGGAGGAGACUCGACAACAUGUCACCCGCGCUCCAAGACCUGUCGCAACCCGGUCUGAAGAAAACCCUGCGGGAUGAGAUCAAUGCCAUUCUGCAGAAGAGGAUUAUGGUGCUGGAUGGAGGGAUGGGGACCAUGAUCCAGCGGGAGAAGCUAAACGAAGAACACUUCCGAGGUCAGGAAUUUAAAGAUCAUGCCAGGCCGCUGAAAGGCAACAAUGACAUUUUAAGUAUAACUCAGCCUGAUGUCAUUUACCAAAUCCAUAAGGAAUACUUGCUGGCUGGGGCAGAUAUCAUUGAAACAAAUACUUUUAGCAGCACUAGUAUUGCCCAAGCUGACUAUGGCCUUGAACACUUGGCCUACCGGAUGAACAUGUGCUCUGCAGGAGUGGCCAGAAAAGCUGCCGAGGAGGUAACUCUCCAGACAGGAAUUAAGAGGUUUGUGGCAGGGGCUCUGGGUCCGACUAAUAAGACACUCUCUGUGUCCCCAUCUGUGGAAAGGCCGGAUUAUAGGAACAUCACAUUUGAUGAGCUUGUUGAAGCAUACCAAGAGCAGGCCAAAGGACUUCUGGAUGGCGGGGUUGAUAUCUUACUCAUUGAAACUAUUUUUGAUACUGCCAAUGCCAAGGCAGCCUUGUUUGCACUCCAAAAUCUUUUUGAGGAGAAAUAUGCUCCCCGGCCUAUCUUUAUUUCAGGGACGAUCGUUGAUAAAAGUGGGCGGACUCUUUCCGGACAGACAGGAGAGGGAUUUGUCAUCAGCGUGUCUCAUGGAGAACCACUCUGCAUUGGAUUAAAUUGUGCUUUGGGUGCAGCUGAAAUGAGACCUUUUAUUGAAAUAAUUGGAAAAUGUACAACAGCCUAUGUCCUCUGUUAUCCCAAUGCAGGUCUUCCCAACACCUUUGGUGACUAUGAUGAAACGCCUUCUAUGAUGGCCAAGCACCUAAAGGAUUUUGCUAUGGAUGGCUUGGUCAAUAUAGUUGGAGGAUGCUGUGGGUCAACACCAGAUCAUAUCAGGGAAAUUGCUGAAGCUGUGAAAAAUUGUAAGCCUAGAGUUCCACCUGCCACUGCUUUUGAAGGACAUAUGUUACUGUCUGGUCUAGAGCCCUUCAGGAUUGGACCGUACACCAACUUUGUUAACAUUGGAGAGCGCUGUAAUGUUGCAGGAUCAAGGAAGUUUGCUAAACUCAUCAUGGCAGGAAACUAUGAAGAAGCCUUGUGUGUUGCCAAAGUGCAGGUGGAAAUGGGAGCCCAGGUGUUGGAUGUCAACAUGGAUGAUGGCAUGCUAGAUGGUCCAAGUGCAAUGACCAGAUUUUGCAACUUAAUUGCUUCCGAGCCAGACAUCGCAAAGGUACCUUUGUGCAUCGACUCCUCCAAUUUUGCUGUGAUUGAAGCUGGGUUAAAGUGCUGCCAAGGGAAGUGCAUUGUCAAUAGCAUUAGUCUGAAGGAAGGAGAGGACGACUUCUUGGAGAAGGCCAGGAAGAUUAAAAAGUAUGGAGCUGCUAUGGUGGUCAUGGCUUUUGAUGAAGAAGGACAGGCAACAGAAACAGACACAAAAAUCAGAGUGUGCACCCGGGCCUACCAUCUGCUUGUGAAAAAACUGGGCUUUAAUCCAAAUGACAUUAUUUUUGACCCUAAUAUCCUAACCAUUGGGACUGGAAUGGAGGAACACAACUUGUAUGCCAUUAAUUUUAUCCAUGCAACAAAAGUCAUUAAAGAAACAUUACCUGGAGCCAGAAUAAGUGGAGGUCUUUCCAACUUGUCCUUCUCCUUCCGAGGAAUGGAAGCCAUUCGAGAAGCAAUGCAUGGGGUUUUCCUUUACCAUGCAAUCAAGUCUGGCAUGGACAUGGGGAUAGUGAAUGCUGGAAACCUCCCUGUGUAUGAUGAUAUCCAUAAGGAACUUCUGCAGCUCUGUGAAGAUCUCAUCUGGAAUAAAGACCCUGAGGCCACUGAGAAGCUCUUACGUUAUGCCCAGACUCAAGGCACAGGAGGGAAGAAAGUCAUUCAGACUGAUGAGUGGAGAAAUGGCCCUGUCGAAGAACGCCUUGAGUAUGCCCUUGUGAAGGGCAUUGAAAAACAUAUUAUUGAGGAUACUGAGGAAGCCAGGUUAAACCAAAAAAAAUAUCCCCGACCUCUCAAUAUAAUUGAAGGACCCCUGAUGAAUGGAAUGAAAAUUGUUGGUGAUCUUUUUGGAGCUGGAAAAAUGUUUCUACCUCAGGUUAUAAAGUCAGCCCGGGUUAUGAAGAAGGCUGUUGGCCACCUUAUCCCUUUCAUGGAAAAAGAAAGAGAAGAAACCAGAGUGCUUAACGGCACAGUAGAAGAAGAGGACCCUUACCAGGGCACCAUCGUGCUGGCCACUGUUAAAGGCGACGUGCACGACAUAGGCAAGAACAUAGUUGGAGUAGUCCUUGGCUGCAAUAAUUUCCGAGUUAUUGAUUUAGGAGUCAUGACUCCAUGUGAUAAGAUACUGAAAGCUGCUCUUGACCACAAAGCAGAUAUAAUUGGCCUGUCAGGACUCAUCACUCCUUCCCUGGAUGAAAUGAUUUUUGUUGCCAAGGAAAUGGAGAGAUUAGCUAUAAGGAUUCCAUUGUUGAUUGGAGGAGCAACCACUUCAAAAACCCACACAGCAGUUAAAAUAGCUCCGAGAUACAGUGCACCUGUAAUCCAUGUCCUGGACGCGUCCAAGAGUGUGGUGGUGUGUUCCCAGCUGUUAGAUGAAAAUCUAAAGGAUGAAUACUUUGAGGAAAUCAUGGAAGAAUAUGAAGAUAUUAGACAGGACCAUUAUGAGUCUCUCAAGGAGAGGAGAUACUUACCCUUAAGUCAAGCCAGAAAAAGUGGUUUCCAAAUGGAUUGGCUGUCUGAACCUCACCCAGUGAAGCCCACGUUUAUUGGGACCCAGGUCUUUGAAGACUAUGACCUGCAGAAGCUGGUGGACUACAUUGACUGGAAGCCUUUCUUUGAUGUCUGGCAGCUCCGGGGCAAGUACCCGAAUCGAGGCUUUCCCAAGAUAUUUAACGACAAAACAGUAGGUGGAGAGGCCAGGAAGGUCUACGAUGAUGCCCACAAUAUGCUGAACACACUGAUUAGUCAAAAGAAACUCCGGGCCCGGGGUGUGGUUGGGUUCUGGCCAGCACAGAGUAUCCAAGACGACAUUCACCUGUACGCAGAGGCUGCUGUGCCCCAGGCUGCAGAGCCCAUAGCCACCUUCUAUGGGUUAAGGCAACAGGCUGAGAAGGACUCUGCCAGCACGGAGCCAUACUACUGCCUCUCAGACUUCAUCGCUCCCUUGCAUUCUGGCAUCCGUGACUACCUGGGCCUGUUUGCCGUUGCCUGCUUUGGGGUAGAAGAGCUGAGCAAGGCCUAUGAGGAUGAUGGUGACGACUACAGCAGCAUCAUGGUCAAGGCGCUGGGGGACCGGCUGGCAGAGGCCUUUGCAGAAGAGCUCCAUGAAAGAGUUCGCCGAGAACUGUGGGCCUACUGUGGCAGUGAGCAGCUGGACGUCGCAGACCUGCGCAGGCUGCGGUACAAGGGCAUCCGCCCGGCUCCUGGCUACCCCAGCCAGCCCGACCACACCGAGAAGCUCACCAUGUGGAGACUCGCAGACAUCGAGCAGUCUACAGGCAUUAGGUUAACAGAAUCAUUAGCAAUGGCACCUGCUUCAGCAGUCUCAGGCCUCUACUUCUCCAAUUUGAAGUCCAAAUAUUUUGCUGUGGGGAAGAUUUCCAAGGAUCAGGUUGAGGAUUAUGCAUUGAGGAAGAACAUAUCUGUGGCUGAGGUUGAGAAAUGGCUUGGACCCAUUUUGGGAUAUGAUACAGACUAACUUUUUUUUUUUUUUUGCCUUUUUUAUUCUUGAUGAUCCUCAAGGAAAUACAACCUAGGGUGCCUUAAAAAUAACAACAACAAAAAACCUGUGUGCAUCUGGCUGACACUUACCUGCUUCUGGUUUUCGAAGACUAUUUAGUGGAACCUUGUAGAGGAGCAGGGUCUUCCUGCAGUGCCUGGAAAACAGGCGCUGUUUUUUUGGGACCUUGCGUGAAGAGCAGUGAGCAGGGUUCCUGUGGUUUCCCUGGUCCCUCUGAGAUGGGGACAGACUGAAGACAGAGGUCGUUUGAUUUCAAAGCAAGUCAACCUGCUUUUUUCUGUUUUUACAGUGGAAUCUAGGAGGCCACUUAGUCGUCUUUUUUUCCUCUUAGAAGAAAAGCCUGAAACUGAGUUGAAUAGAGAAGUGUGACCCUGUGACAAAAUGAUACUGUGAGAAAUGGGGCAUUUUAAUCUAAGUGGUUAUAACAGUGGAUUCUGACGGGGAAGGUGUAGCUCUGUUCUCUUCGGAAGACCUCGUUUUCUAAAGGCUGGACUAAAUGGCUGCAGAACUCCCUUUGGCAAAAGGCAUGCGCUCACUGCUUGCUUGUCAGAAACACUGAAGCCAUUUGCCCCAGUGUGGUCAAGCAGCCAUGCUUUCUGGGCAUUUUCGUCCUCCCAUAAUUUCAUAUUUCCGUACCCCUGAGGAAACAAAAAGGAAAUGAGGAGAGAAAGUUACUGUUAAGGGUGGUUAACAUUUUUUUUGUUUUGUUUUGUUUUGGUUUUUUUUUUUUUGAGACAGAGUCUGGCUCUGUCGCCCAGGCUGGAGUGCAGGGGCGCAAUCUCGGCUCAUAGCAAGCUCCGCCUCCUGGGUUCAUGCCAUUCUCCUGCCUCAGCCUCCAGAGUAGCUGGGACUACAGGUGCCCGCCACCACACCCGGCUAAUUUUUUGUGUUUUUACAAAAUACAAAAAAGUAGAGACAGGAUUUCACUGUGUUAGCCAGGAUGGUCUUGAUCUCCCGACCUCGUGAUCUGCCCACCUCAGCCUCCCAAAAUGCUGGGAUUACAGGCGUGAGCCACCGAGCCUGGCCGGUUAACAUCUUUUAAUUGUUUCCAGGAUUGAGCAGGUUCUCAGCUGGGCUCUGAUAUCCCGUGCGGAGUUGGACAAGUGGGCAGCAUAAAGUCACUCAUUUCUUACCAUUUUAUUCCCCUCAAUUCUCAAUAUAUUCAGUAAUGAAGAAUGGUGCCACCACUCAAGCAACAAGCCUCAAACUCAACCAUGUCAUCUUUUUCUUGGAUGAUUGCAGUUAUUUCAAAAAUUUGCAUGCAAAAUAUACACUCAUCCUACUUCAAGAUGGUGGUGGCAAUAGUCAGGAGAAGGUAACAUUGGAGUCCUGGUUUGAUUCGAAGGAUGAAGACGAAGAAGCAAGGGAGGAACAAAUGAAGAACCAUCUUUGUUCAUGAAUAGGAAUAUUCAAGAUUAUAAAGGUAUCAGGUCUCCUAAAAUUGAUCUAUGGAUUUAAUACCAUUUUCAAUGGAAAUUCCAACAGAUUUUAUUGAAUGAAACAAGCAGGUGUUUAUAUGGAGUAGCAAAGGACUUAAAAUUACCAAAUGCUUCUAAAUAUGAAGGAGAGGUUGGGGACACGCACCCUAUGUGAUACCAAGUUUUAUUGUCAAGACAGUGUCAUGGUGCAGAGGUAGGCAUUCUGAGCAGGGGAACAAAAUAAGGGCCUAGAAACUCACCCGUGCAUAUGUUGACCUUUGCAAAAUGACCUGGUGACAUGGCAAGUCAGUGGGGACAGGAAGGACCACUCCCUAAGUAAUCCCAGAACAAUGGCUAUUCAUGUGGGAAAAAAAGAAAUUUUACUUUCUCUCACCUUACCUGGUGAUAAGUUCCAAAUAUGUUAAGGGCUUUAAUACAAAAAGCAAAAAUUGUCAGUGUUUGGAUGAAAAAAGCCUUAGGGCAGGAAAGAAUCUCUUGAGACAUAAAGUAGUAAUCAUAAAGGACAAGAUGGUUAAGUCAAUUCUGUUAAAACUCAAGGCUUAUAUUAAGCAAACACUUGAAGUGAGAAGAUGAUCCACAACUUGAGAAGACAUUUAUAAUACAAAUAACUGAUGAAGGAUUCAUAAUCACAAAUAUAGAGAAUUCCUAUUUAAAAAAAUAGAAAAAUAGUGAAGACUACACAAGAGGAAAUAGGGCUUUUAAAUAAAUAGAUGUUCUGUAGCAUUGGUCAGGGAAAUAUGAAUUAGGACCACAAUGAGAUUCCAUUUUAUAUCCAUAAGAUUUGCAAAGGUUGGGUCUGACAGUACCAGUUGUUAGAUCUGUAGGGACUUGUACAACAUUGUGGAUGUGUAAACAGGCACCACUGCUUUAAAAAACAAUUAUCCCUUACAGACUUGAACAUUUGCAGACGUUAUGAUCUUGCUUCCAACUCCCACCUGUAUGUCCAGCAAACUCUUGCAUGUGGCCACUAGGAGGAAUGUGUAAGAAUGUUCAUAGUUACAUAUUUAUAAUAGUUAAUAACUGGAAAAAGUGAAAUGUAUGUCUGUCUACAGGAAAAUAGGUGAAUAAUUAGAUAUAUAUAUUCAUUCUACGGGAUAUUAUUCAGUAGUGGAAAUGAGUGAACUACAGCUAUACCUCACAAUAAGAAUGAAUCUCAGAAAAUAUUAAGGAAAAAAGCAAGUUUGAAGAGACCACAUGGGGCGUACUAUUUUUAUUGAGCCCAAAAACAAGCAAAACCAAAGAAUAUGUAGUCUAAGCAUACGUAUACAAUAAAACUAUGCUAUUAAAAAAAAAGAAGGUAACUGAUAAACCAAAAUUGAGCAUAGUAAUUACCCACAGAAGGAGGAAGUGGAAGGGACAGGAGCACAUAGGUAGAUGCCAAGUUAUGCAGCUGUUCUGGUUCCUCCUGGUAGGCUUACAAGUGUUUACUAUAUGCUAUUAAUACAUUAUACUUUAUAACUAAUAGAUAACAGUUUUUUACAUAUUAAAUAUGUUCUACUUAAAUAUAUUAUAAAAAAUAAAGGCAAAGUGGAAUGAUAACCUAAAAUCUGGUAUGGUGAUUUUGUAGGUAAUGUUUGUAUAUGUCAAAUACAGUUUUUAAGGAAAGGAAGAACAUCUUAGGGUAAACAGCAGCUAGAAAGGUGAGGGGCAGGAGAGUGGUGCAUCCUUGCUGCUGCCAGCAGUGCCCAGAUACCAGGCUUUGGGGAAUGAGUGGAUGGCUGGACCAUUUGCUAAGACAGAGGCCAGGGGAUGGGAGAAAUGAUGAGUUUUGGAAAGAUUCGAUGUGACUAGACUGAAUAUAGGCAGUUGGAUACUAGACUUUGGAAUUUAAAAAGAAUGUCUGGAGUUAGAAUUGAGAGACUUGAACGUGGAGAUGGAGGUCAGGCUGCAGUGCGAUGGGAUCAUCUAUGGAGCAUAUGAGGAGAAGAGAAUCUGGAGGAGGAGGAGGGGGAGCCAGCAGGGGAGCAGCUGUGGGUUGGAGGAAGCCAGGAGGGAGAGUGCAAUGCCGAGAAAGCAAUGAAGAGCGUUUCGAAGCAUGCCAGCAGAACCCAAUGCUGCAAAGAGGCCUGGGAAUGGGAUUGCUGAGGGCCCUUCUCACAGUGAGCCCCUCAAGAGCAGCGUCAGGGGAUUGUGGGGACUGUUGGCACACAGCUGGCUUUGCUAGGUUGAAGACAAUGGGAGGUGUGGAAGACUUGUUGACUCAUUUAAAGAAGAUUGGAGGGAAAGGUAGGAUUGAGAGUGUUUCAGACAGAAAAAGGAUUAUAUGCUGAGGGUAAAGCACAAGUACAGAGGGUUGCAGAUAGUGCAGAAGUCUUUAAAAACAAUUAUUUUAACCCAACUUCCAGGGAGACUGAAUUUCUUCUGCCAGUCAGUAACACCAUCAACCUGGGAGUUGCCCCUGACCCCUCCAGUCUUAGCUCCUGCUCCUGUAACAAAAUACCACAAACUGGUUAGCUUAUAGAGAACAGAUGUUUAUUUCUUACAGUUCAGGAGUCUGGAAGUCCAAGAUCAUGGUGCCAUCAUGGCCGAGUUCUGGUGAGGGCCCUCUUCUGGGAUGCAGCGGCCAGCUUCUCAUGUUCUCACAGUGGGUGGAGGGUAAGCUUGCUCUCUGGCCUCCUCUUAAAAAGGCACUAAUCCCAUUCAUGAGGGCUCCACCUUCAUGACCUAAUUACCUCCCAAAGAUGCCAUCUCCAAACACCAUCAUUCUGGGGAUUCCAUUUCAACAUGAUUUGGGGGAUACAUCAGACCAUAACACUUUUCUUUUUCUCAACCUUCACAUCCAGUUGGUUCUCAAGCCCUGGCGAUUUUACGCGCUAGAUAGGUCUUAAGUUCAUCUCUACGCCUGCCCUGGUUAAGGUUCUCAUCAUUUCUCCUCUGGAUUCAUCUGCAACACAGGCUGCCGGGUUGGUUCCCACCUCCUAGAGCUGGAAGAGUGGGCUCUCUGAUUCUUUACACCCCCGCCUCAAUCCUCCUGCUGCCUGAAUAACCAUCUCCCCGUGACCUAGGAUAUAUCCCAGCCCCUUAGAGGCAUGCAAAGCCUUCCAUGUCUGACCCUGCCUCAUGUCUUGGAAGCCCUAGACUGCUGCUGUACCCUGAAGGAGGUACCUGCUCACAUUGGCCCCUCUGUCUGGAAUAACCCCACCCCGGUUCCACCCAAGUCAGGAAAGCUUCCCAACCCCUCCCUCCCACCACCCCAAAGCUAAGUGAAGUGACCCCUCUUCUUGCCUCUGUAACACCGCCAUGCACAUUUCAUACAGCCCUUGCUGAAACUUCAUCUAGUUCUCUGUUAGACUUAACAUUCCCUAAGGGCAGGUUUGGAACCUUACUCAUCUUUAUAUGGCGUCUAAAAUAGUGCUUGCUUUAUGAUAGGUGCUCAGUAAAGGUUGUCUUGAAUUGAGCAGAUCCUCUAGGGACAGGAGUUGGAUGGAGAGCAGACUGUAAAGCCUCAUGAGGGCAGGGGCCCUGCCUCUUCCUGAGCUCAGGAUACCCAGAGCCUAGCUCAGUGCCUGCCAUGAAAUUGUUCACUCCAUCAAGCCUUGUUAAAUGAGUUCGGGGCGGGGGGAGCAUGAUGGUUUUCUCUCUCUCAGAAAGAAAGCGCUGUAUCAAAGCCCUAGCACCCUCUCUACACCCACCUUCAGUAUUUCAUAUUAGAUGCGGCCCAAGUGAUACUUUCUUUACCGUCCCGUGAAGACAGCAUAUUGGCAGCCCUGCAAAAACAAAACAAAACAAAACCCUCAGUUCAUGGCAUACUUGCUAUAAAUCAGCUAUGUGUAUUGUCAAAUUGUAGAACUGAAAGUAUAUUCUGAUUCGGUGUGUGUAUAAGGAAAUAUACACCAGUAUAUGCAUUAAAACGUCAAGAAGAGCUGGGCACAGUGUCACAUGCCUGUAAACCCAGCUAUUCAGGAGGCUGAGGUGGGAGGAUCGGUUGAGGCCAGGAGUUUGAGGCUGCAGUGAGCUAUGAUUGCACAGCUGCACUCCAGCCUGUGCUGAGACCUCAUCUCUUAAAAAAUAAAAAAUAAAAAGUCUAAGAGGAUACACAGAAAUUUUUAAGUGGUUACCUCCACGGAAUGGGAUUAGGGGAUCAGAGGUGAGGGAACUCAUGGUUUGGCUAUUUCUCGUUCUUUCUGCACUGUUUCAAAUUUUUACAAGUGUAUGUUAUUGUACUUUUAAAAAGAUUAGCUUGGCAACAAGUCUAGCCUGAAAUGGGUGCUAUUUUGACUAGUCUGAGUGAAAAGUGAGGAUUUAAAUGAAGUAACCCCUAAACUCAGCCAGUCCCAUGUUUUUUUAACACUUGGAAUAUCUAAUUCCAUUUACACUGCAUUCUUCAAAUGUAAUUUUCAAAGAUGCCUUUUGCCUCAUCCCUUGCUUUUAAGUAUUAUUAUAGACUUUUGGAGACUCACGAAACAAGCAAUCCCUAAAUUCUCGCCCAGGAAAGUAUCUUGGAUUAAAUGGUUUUUGAGAACCUUGAGAGUGUAUAUUCUAUGAAAUGGAAGAAACAAGAACUAGACAGAGUCACAAAUGCUGUUGAUCACAGACAAUCUCUGCCAUCCAUAAGGUAAAUGUAAUACAUCUGGCGACCUGCUGAGUGUGAACUUGCAGCAGGUGAGGAAGGAACUCUGAACUCUCACAAUCUUGUUUCUUCAUUUCCCAGAGAGAAACUCGGCAAAGAGAAAAAGGACAUUUCCCUCCAGGUUAUCUGAAAGAAUUUCAAUGCUUACCUUUAAUCAUGUGACAUUGUUUAUCUUGGAUUAAAAGAAAAGAAAAUGUAUUUAUUUUGUGCAUAUUUUCAAUAAAAUAUAUAAAAUCGAGUUGGUAUAUAGUGCCAAAUACCAUUAAUUAAAAAUAUUUUAACCUGA